GCAUUUAUAACUCUGUAAGAGUUUAGGAUAGUUUAGUUAUGAGUGACAGAAAAAUCUAAAGCAAACUGGCUUAUACCAAAGAGAACUAAUCAGCCAUGUUGAGCAUGACUGAUUCCCUUGUGGUAGCAAGAUGGCCACCUCCCACACUCACACCAAAUUCUGUGGAAGCAAGAGAGUCCCUUCCUGGCAUUCCUGAGCAAGUAAGUCCUCACAUUUGCUUAGGAAUGCCUGAAAGGAUACUCAUGUCCAUUUGUUAAUAGGAAUCGAUGAACAAAUGUACAUGAGUAUCCUUUUUUUUCUGGUAUCAAUAUGUUUAAUUGAUUAUUAUUGCAAAAGAACAGUUUUCCUGGCCAGGUGCGGUGGCUCACGCCUAUAAUCCCAGCACUUUGGGAGGCCGAGGUGGGCGGAUCACAAGGUCAGGAGUUUGAGACCAGCCUGGCCAAUAUUGUGAAACCCUGUCGCUACUAAAAAUACAAAAAUUAGCCAGGCAUGAUGGUGCGCGCCUGUAGUCCCAGCUACUUAGGAGGCUGAGGCAGGAGAAUCGCUUGAACCCAGGAGGCGGAAGUUGGAGUGAGCCGAGAUUGAGCCACUGCACUCCAGCCUGGUGACAAAGCAAGACUCCAUUUCAAAAAAAAAAAAAAAAAAAAAAGGCUGGCACAGUGGCUCAUGCCUGUAAUCCCAGCACUUUGGGAGGCCGAGGCAGGCCGAUCCCCUGAGGUUGAGAGUUCGAGACCAGCCUAACAUGGAGAAACCCCGUCUCUACUAAAAAUACAAAAUUAGCCGGGCGUGGAGGUGCAGGCCUGUAAUCCCAGCUACUUGGGAGGCUGAGGCAGGAGAAUCACUUGAACCCGGGAGGCGGAGGUUGCAGUGAGCCAAGAUAGCGCCAUUGCACUCCAGCCUGGGCGACAGAGCGAAACUCCGUCUCAAAAAAAAAAAAAAAAAAAGAACAGUUUUCCUAUGAUUAGUGAAAUAGAAAACUCACAAUAUAGUCAUGCCAGAACCACCUUCUGGAACCAGAAAGAUGGAAUAUGCCAUUUUGCUUAGCUUUGUUGAAGAGAAGGGAUGGCUGUCAUGAAGCACAAUUGGGAUGAUAUUUCCAGAAGCUGAGGGAAUGGAUACUAGGGAGCACAAGGGGAAGUGCCCUCUAGAGCAGGGGUCGCCAACCCCCUCGGGGUACCAGUCCGUGUCCUGUUCGGAACUGGGCCGCACAGCAGGAGGUGAGCAGUGGGCGAGGGAGCAUUACCACCUGAGUUCCGCCUUCUGUCAGAUCAGCCACAGCAUCAGAUUCUCACAGAAGCUCGAACCCUAUUGUGGAUUGCACAUGCGCGGGAUCUCGGCUGCGCGCUCCUCACGAGAAUCAUAUCACUUCCUGAUGGCCUGAGGUGGAACGGUUUCAUCUCGAAACUACUCCCCAUCAUCCGUGGAAAAAUUGCCUUCCACAAGCCUGUCCCUGGUACCAAAAAAGUUGGGGACCACGCCUGUAAUCCCAGAACUUUGGGAGGCCGAGGCGGGCGGAUCACGAGGUCAGGAGAUCGAGACCAUCCUGGCUAACACGGUGAAACCCCGUCUCUACUAAAAAUACAAAAAAAUUAGCCGGGCGUGGUGGCGGGUGCCUGUAGUCCCAGCUACUCGAGGCUGAGGCAGGAGAAUGGCGUGAACCCGGGAGGUGGAGCUUGCAGUGAGCCUAGAUCGCGCCACUGCACUCCAGCCUGGGCGACAGAGCGAGACUCCAUCUCAAAAAAAAGAAAAAAGAAAAGUUGGGGACCGCUGCUGUACGGGAGCCAACAGCUCUCUAACUAAUACUUAAAAAUAGAACCUCACCUUACCCCUCUUUCUUUAUCCUCCUCAUGGCCUAGCACACAGCUCUAGGUCUAUGGACACUUAUUUUAAAAUGCAACAGCUAUAGACAUGCUCGGUGGUGGGGAGGGGCUAUAGAAGAAUUCAUCCAGAAACAUGGCACCAACUUUCUCAAAGAUCAUCGAUUUGGGUCAUAUGCUGCUAUCCAAGAGAAUGCUUUAGCUAAAUGGUAUGUUAAUGCCAAAGGAUAUUUUGAAGAUGUGGCAAAUGCAAUGGAAGAGGCAAAUGAAGAGAUUUUUAUCACAGACUGGUGGCUGAGUCCAGAAAUCUUCCUGAAACGCCCAGUGGUUGAGGGAAAUCGUUGGAGGUUGGACUGCAUUCUUAAACGAAAAGCACAACAAGGAGUGAGGAUCUUCAUAAUGCUCUACAAAGAGGUGGAACUCGCUCUUGGCAUCAAUAGUGAAUACACCAAGAGGACUUUGAUGCGUCUACAUCCCAACAUAAAGGUGAUGAGACACCCGGAUCAUGUGUCAUCCACCGUCUAUUUGUGGGCUCACCAUGAGAAGCUUGUCAUCAUUGACCAAUCGGUGGCCUUUGUGGGAGGGAUUGACCUGGCCUAUGGAAGGUGGGACGACAAUGAGCACAGACUCACAGACGUGGGCAGUGUGAAGCGGGUCACUUCAGGACCGUCUCUGGGUUCCCUCCCACCUGCCGCAAUGGAGUCUAUGGAAUCCUUAAGACUCAAAGAUAAAAAUGAGCCUGUUCAAAACCUACCCAUCCAGAAGAGUAUUGAUGAUGUGGAUUCAAAACUGAAAGGAAUAGGAAAGCCAAGAAAGUUCUCCAAAUUUAGUCUCUACAAGCAGCUCCACAGGCACCACCUGCACGACGCAGAUAGCAUCAGCAGCAUUGACAGCACCUCCAGUUAUUUUAAUCACUAUAGAAGUCAUCACAAUUUAAUCCAUGGUUUAAAACCCCACUUCAAACUCUUUCACCCGUCCAGUGAGUCUGAGCAAGGACUCACUAGACCUCAUGCUGAUACCGGGUCCAUCCGUAGUUUACAGACAGGUGUGGGAGAGCUGCAUGGGGAAACCAGAUUCUGGCAUGGAAAGGACUACUGCAAUUUCGUCUUCAAAGACUGGGUUCAACUUGAUAAACCUUUUGCUGAUUUCAUUGACAGGUACUCCACGCCCCGGAUGCCCUGGCAUGACAUUGCCUCUGCAGUCCACGGGAAGGCGGCUCGUGAUGUGGCACGUCACUUCAUCCAGCGCUGGAACUUCACAAAAAUUAUGAAAUCAAAAUAUCGGUCCCUUUCUUAUCCUUUUCUGCUUCCAAAGUCUCAAACAACAGCCCAUGAGUUGAGAUAUCAAGUGCCUGGGUCUGUCCAUGCUAACGUACAGUUGCUCCGCUCUGCUGCUGAUUGGUCUGCUGGUAUAAAGUACCAUGAAGAGUCCAUCCACGCCGCUUACGUCCAUGUGAUAGAGAACAGCAGGCACUAUAUCUAUAUCGAAAACCAGUUUUUCAUAAGCUGUGCUGAUGACAAAGUUGUGUUCAACAAGAUAGGCGAUGCCAUUGCCCAGAGGAUCCUGAAAGCUCACAGGGAAAACCAGAAAUACCGGGUAUAUGUCGUGAUACCACUUCUGCCAGGGUUCGAAGGAGACAUUUCAACCGGCGGAGGAAAUGCUCUACAGGCAAUCAUGCACUUCAACUACAGAACCAUGUGCAGAGGAGAAAAUUCCAUCCUUGGACAGUUAAAAGCAGAGCUUGGUAAUCAGUGGAUAAAUUACAUAUCAUUCUGUGGUCUUAGAACACAUGCAGAGCUCGAAGGAAACCUAGUAACUGAGCUUAUCUAUGUCCACAGCAAGUUGUUAAUUGCUGAUGAUAACACUGUUAUUAUUGGCUCUGCCAACAUAAAUGACCGCAGCAUGCUGGGAAAGCGUGACAGUGAAAUGGCUGUCAUUGUGCAAGAUACAGAGACUGUUCCUUCAGUAAUGGAUGGAAAAGAGUACCAAGCUGGCCGGUUUGCCCGAGGACUUCGGCUACAGUGCUUUAGGGUUGUCCUUGGCUAUCUUGAUGACCCAAGUGAGGACAUUCAGGAUCCAGUGAGUGACAAAUUCUUCAAGGAGGUGUGGGUUUCAACAGCAGCUCGAAAUGCUACAAUUUAUGACAAGGUUUUCCGGUGCCUUCCCAAUGAUGAAGUACACAAUUUAAUUCAGCUGAGAGACUUUAUAAACAAGCCCGUAUUAGCUAAGGAAGAUCCCAUUCGAGCUGAGGAGGAACUGAAGAAGAUCCGUGGAUUUUUGGUGCAAUUCCCCUUUUAUUUCUUGUCUGAAGAAAGCCUACUGCCUUCUGUUGGGACCAAAGAGGCCAUAGUGCCCAUGGAGGUUUGGACUUAAGAGAUAUUCAUUGGCAGCUCAAAGACUUCCACCCUGGAGACCACACUGCACACAGUGACUUCCUGGGGAUGUCAUAGCCAAAGCCAGGCCUGACGCAUUCUCGUAUCCAACCCAAGGACCUUUUGGAAUGACUGGGGAGGGCUGCAGUCACAUUGAUGUAAGGACUGUAAACAUCAGCAAGACUUUAUAAUUCCUUCUGCCUAACUUGUAAAAAGGGGGCUGCAUUCUUGUUGGUAGCAUGUACUCUGUUGAGUAAAACACAUAUUCAAAUUCCGUAUACCAAAAUCCAUUUCCUUUGUAACAAGAAUUUACCAGUAACUGUGAUCUAGGUUGCCAAAAGUUGUCUGAAUCUCCUUAUUCUUCUCUGAUCUUCAUUUAUGCAGCCAAUGUCUAGCUGGACCUGCCCUCAUCUUGCAGUUCAUACAGGCACUGUUUGAGAGAUUGUUUAUUAUUAGAUGUUGUAAUGCUGCUUCAAGAUUCUUCAUGGUUACAUGGGAUGCCCCUGCUCAUCUGGUCCUGAAGUAGUAACAUUCACCCAAAUGAGGAUAUAGUCAUUAUUCCUUUUCAGUCACUGUACGAACACGGCAGACUUUAGCCUACACAGUAGACUGUGUUAGGCACUUCUGGUAACAUUGACACUGUAUCUUGACACCACUAAGCAACAGGAAGGAAUAAAUUCCAAUAUUGAGACAGAGAUUUAUUUCAUUUUGCUCCCAAAGGCACUGACAACAUGAGUCCUUGUGAUUAGGCCCACCUGAUCAAAUGUAAAAACAUGCAUGGGAUAUUUGAUUACGUAACAACCAGCUAAAACUGAGAGCACACAGCCUUCGGAAACCCCCAAGGUGUCGAGGAGGAUCAGAUCCAGAUAAGAGAAGAUGAUUCCUUCUAGUCCUGUAAAAUUUCCUGUCAUCCUUAGCUGCUGGGUUGAUUGAAAUUUGAUCUCUACAUUUCAAAAUCAAACUAGUGAAUACAGUUUGUCUUUCAAGAGAAUCAGAGGCAUCGUAACUCCUACCAAGUUAGUAAGUAUGAGUCUAACCUUGUUUGACAUUCAGGUCUUCUGCUACAUUAUCUUCUUUGAGAAAAAUUAAUUGAUUAUAAAAUAUGUGCUACUUCACUUACAUUAUUAAAUAUGUAUUAACGCCUCUCACCAGGGCUUCCAGUGAAGUUACAAUGCCCUAGUCUGUGAAUUAGUCUGGAAACGUGUUUUUCCUUUUCGGAUGUUAGAGUACCCUUUGAUAAACUAAAUUUUACUAAGCUGAACAACUCUGACAGUCUAAAGAGCUAAUGUGGGUUACCAAAAGGCCUGUACCUGUAAAACAAAAUGCAGGUGUAAUGAUUAUACAUGUCUAUGGAUUACCUGGACAUACUCUCAUUUGGGUUGUUCUUCAAAGAAGCAAGCAGCCGAUCCCUGUUUUCAUAAAGCUAAUACUUCAGUUGGAAAAAUUAAACAGGAGCACAAAGUCAGGGAUAGGGGUUAGCAGAAGAGAGAAAUAGUGUCACAUCAAGGGCAGGAUCUCAUAGCUAGGGAACAUUUCACAAAUAAGGUGAGAUUUUGUAACCAAUAAUAAAAAUGAAUGUUUUUAUAAGUAAAUAACUUAUUUUUCAUAUGGCUAAAGAUGGUAAAAUGACUUCAUUCUAUAGCCAUUGUAAAUAAGAAUUUGCUAUUGAUGAAAGAAGUUCAGAUUGGCAUUUGAAGUAUUGAGUGUAUGGGAUCUCUAAGGAUUUCUUAGAUUUUAUAUUUAAAUAUUUUUUAAACCUUAGAGGAGUCAACAAACUGGCUCUUGAUUUUCAGCACCCUACUCUCAUGAAAAAAGCCUGAAAGGACCCUUUCCCUUAUAAGUAAUUUAAUCCAAUUUCUCCCCAUUUUAUAGAUGAGGAAACUGAGGCUCAGAUCAGAUGAGAACUCACUUAAAUCCACUCAAUGUGUAGAUGGUAGAGCUGGGACUAGCAACAUUGCUGCAGCCCAUUGUUGGCCUCUCUCUUCACUUUAUCAUUGCCCAAGAAUGAGGAUAUGCAGUAAACAGAAUUCAGGCAAGAUACCUCUAAGCUGUUUUGAACCCUCUGAUAUUUUGUAUUUAUGUGUUUGUCUGUCUCCCCCUACUAGAAUGUAAGCUCCAUGGGGCAGGGACUUCACUGUAUUUUGUUCAUAGUGUAUCCCCAGAGCCUGGACCAGUGCUUGGCACAUAGGAGAUGGCAAUAAAUGCUUGUAGAAUUAAUAAACAAGGUGAAGGAGAGAGCUAAUGAAAUGAAAAUCUUAGUCUCAUAUAAGAAGUCUUACUACUGCUUUCUAUGGCAAGUUCCUUUUCUAUUGCAUCUUCCCAAAGACAAGAUGCUCAUCUGCAAAGGGGUGAUAAGAUUUACUUGGAGGGAUUUUAUGGAAAAUUCAGUGCAAUAAUUGCUUUUUUUUUUUUUUUUGCAGUAGCAGUUUACAUAGUACAGCAUUCUGCAAAAAUUGCAUGAAAUGUGGACACAAGAUGUACUGUAUGACUUAAUUACCUGUCAUUCUCUGACACCAUUACUACCUACUAGAAGUUCAAAUAAUUUAUCUUUAACAUUGCAAUAUCUGAUAAACUUUUUAAAAUGUAAAUAAUUCAAAGCCUUGAAAAUCUAUCAUGAAUCUGCUCAACAUUUCAAAGUGACUAUUUUGAAAUGCCUAUAAAUGCUAUAUACCUGA